GUCUGCCUCCAGGCUUUGUCAUGGCGGCUGCUGCUGCACGCUGGAACCAUGUGUGGGUCGGCACCGAGACUGGGAUCUUGAAAGGGGUAAAUCUUCAGCGAAAACAGGCGGCGAACUUCACGGCCGGAGGACAGCCGCGGCGCGAGGAGGCAGUGAGCGCCCUGUGUUGGGGCACCGGCGGCGAGACCCAGAUGCUGGUGGGCUGCGCGGACAGGACGGUGAAGCACUUCAGCACCGAGGAUGGCAUAUUCCAGGGUCAGAGACACUGCCCGGGCGGGGAGGGCAUGUUCCGUGGCCUCGCCCAGGCCGACGGAGCCUCACUGUGUCACCUAGGCUUGAGUGCAGUGGUGCAUUCAUGGCUCACUACAGCCUCAACCUCCCGGGGUCAAACGAUCCUCCCGCCUCAACCUCCUGAGUACCUGGGACCACAGGCUCAAGCGAUUCUCUUGCCUCAGCCUCCUGAGUAGCUGGGAUUACAGGCAUCCGCCACCACGCCCAGCUAAGUUUUUUUUGUAUUUUUAUUAGAGACAGGGUUUCACUAUGUUGGCCAGGCUAGUCUGGAACUCCUGACCUCAGGCAAUCCGCCCACCUCAGCCUCCCAAAAUGCUGGGAUUACAGGCGUGAACCACUGCACCCGGCCAAGGAAGCAUUUUAAUACAAGAUGAACACUAUAUUAGGUUGGGAUUAAAUGUAAAGGGCUUUAAGUGCUAGGUUGAGAGAUGUGCACUUUUAUUGGUGUUGGUGAGUUAUUCAUUUAUUGUUUUUGUUUUUCUGAGAGACGGAGUCUUGCUCUGUCACUGAGGCUGAAGUGCAGUGGCAUGAUCUCGGCUCACUGCAACCUCCACCUCCCUGGUUCAGGCGAUUCUCCUGCCUCAACUUCCCAAGUAGCUAGGACUACAGCACCCUCAUCACAUGUGUGGAUUCUGGGAUUCUCAGAGUCUGGCAUGACAAGGACAAGGACACAUCCUCUGACCCACUCCUGGAACUGAGAGUGGGCCCUGGGGUGUGUAGGAUGCGCCAAGACCCAGCACACCCCCAUGUGGUUGCCACAGGUGGGAAAGAGAAUGCUUUGAAGAUAUGGGACCUGCAGGGCUCUGAGGAACCUGUGUUCAGGGCCAAGAACGUGCGGAAUGACUGGCUGGACUUGCGGGUUCCCAUCUGGGACCAGGACAUACAGUUUCUCCCAGGAUCACAGAAGCUUGUCACCUGCACAGGGUACCACCAGGUCCGUGUUUAUGAUCCAGCAUCCCCCCAGCGCCGGCCAGUCCUAGAGACCACCUAUGGAGAGUACCCACUAACAGCCAUGACCCUCACUCCGGGAGGCAACUCAGUGAUUGUGGGAAACACUCAUGGGCAGCUGGCAGAAAUUGACCUUCGGCAAGGGCGUCUACUGGGCUGUCUGAAGGGGCUGGCAGGCAGUGUGCGUGGGUUGCAGUGCCACCCUUCAAAGCCUCUACUAGCCUCCUGUGGCUUGGACAGAGUCUUGAGGAUACACAGGAUCCAGAAUCCACGGGGUCUGGAGCAUAAGGUUUAUCUCAAGUCUCAAUUGAACUGCCUCCUCUUGUCAGGCAGGGACAACUGGGAGGAUGAGCCCCAAGAGCCUCAAGAACCCAACAAGGUGCCCCUAGAAGACACAGAGACAGAUGAACUUUGGGCAUCCUUGGAGGCAGCUGCCAAGCGGAAGCUCUCGGGUUUGGAGCAGCCCCAAGGAGCUCUCCAAACGAGACGGAGAAAGAAGAAGCGGCCUGGGUCCACCAGCCCCUGACGCCCCUGUGCCCACUUUGUAAAUAAACUGCUGAACACCCA